AUUUCCUGCCGGUGCCUAGGGCCGACGGGGACGCUGGCACUGGUGGGGAGCUGUUGGGGGGUCCCGCAUCUAGGGCUCUCCUUUCCUGCCUCCGGCCCCCGCGAGGGGCGCGCGCCUCUCCCCGCCCUCCAGCAGUCCUGGUAGGGCCCGGGCGCGUCCGCGCUCUGCAGCGGGAGGUCCUCGUCGCCUCUCGUCUCCAGCCAGCACCAAGAGGAUGGUGGCCCUUGGCCUCCUGGUGCAGAGCAUCAGUCCCACGCUGGGAGUGUGGAGAGGUGCGUGGGAAGCAAGCCAUUGAGGAAGUGGGGCCAACAGAGAGGUCAGCAGCCCCUUAGCCCUCACGCUUCCAAGGAACAGAAUGAUGGAGAAGCCUGCAGGCAGAAAAAAGAAGACGCCGACCCCAAGGGAGGAGGCAGACGUGCAGAAGAGUGCGCUCAGAGAGGAGAAGGUGUCCGGGGACAGAAAGCCACCUGAGAGGCCCACUGUGCCCAGGAAGCCCCGCACAGAGCCCUGCCUGAGUCCUGAAGACGAAGAGCACGUCUUUGAUGCCUUCGACGCUUCAUUUAAAGAUGACUUUGAGGGGGUUCCCGUGUUCAUUCCUUUUCAGAGGAAGAAACCCUAUGAGUGCAGUGAGUGUGGGCGGAUCUUUAAGCACAAGACAGACCACAUUCGCCAUCAGAGGGUCCACACUGGAGAGAAGCCCUUCAAGUGUGCGCAGUGCGGGAAGGCCUUCCGGCACAGCUCUGACGUCACCAAACACCAGAGGACUCACACGGGAGAGAAGCCCUUCAAAUGCGGGGAGUGCGGGAAAGCCUUUAACUGCGGCUCCAAUCUCCUGAAACAUCAGAAGACGCACACCGGGGAGAAGCCCUACGAAUGCACGCACUGUGGGAAAGCCUUUGCCUACAGCUCCUGUCUCAUCCGCCAUCAGAAACGCCACCCUCGGAAGAAGCCCUGAGCCGGGGCCAUCUGCGGACUCGGGCCCUGCGGUGCGAGCCUCGCCGGACACCUGCUCCGUGGCUCCCUCGUGUCCCGCGUCUGAUGGGGGCGCAGGGCCGUGCGCACUGUGUUCCGUGCCCUGGGGACCCCCGGAAAAGCAGCCCAGUCAGAUGUGGGAACGUGCCAGCGAGGGAGAGACCUUUCCACUGCAGAGAGUCUCUCUGAUCAAGACACCGCAGUGAUGGAGAAGCCACCAGAGGCUCCUUGCAGCCACAGAGCAUUUUCCAAGUUCCCGAUGGCGAACGGGGCUCAGCACCAGAGACCAGGGAGUAUUCACUGCCAUCCAUUGGACGUGUUUGGGUCACCUCAGAGCACCCAGCAGGAGAGGCUCCUGGUGUAGUGGGCAGCCCAGCACUUCCCGCUGCUGCCUGCCUGUGAUGUCCACUCUGCUUAAGCCUUUCAUCUGCCGCUGAAGGCCCCAGUCUGGACUCUCUGCCCUCUGGGUCCCCGAGCUCUGCAGCGAGCCCUGGGACCACUCAUCCCUGCCCAGCCAGCUUCAGUGCCCGGGGCCGCUUGUCCCUGCCCGGCCUCUGUGCCCCAACUGUGCUUGGUCCUCUGGCUUCUCUCCUCCUGCUGGAGUGCCAGUCCCUGAGCUCAGACCCCCGUCCCCGGAACUGGGCCACACCACGUGCCCUCUUGGCCCAGCCUUCCUCCCAGAGAGGCGGCCUGACUUACCUGGAUGGACUUGGGACAAAGGUUCCUCAGGACCUUGGACACCACCACCUGCUGAGCUUCCCGUCCCAGCCAUGCAGUGGGGCCCCUGGGGUGCCCUCGGCAGCUUCGGUCCAGCCUGCAUCUGCCCCUCGGCCUUCCGACGUGGGCGGUGGGCCCCAGCCCCACAGACCAGCCCAGCAUUCAGGCUGGUAGAGCAGAUCACCCCCAAAGCAAGAAGUUCCAGAUGAAAUAUGCAUAAGAAGCAGCCUCAAAACUAACAAAAAAGAUUCGCACAUUCCUCAGUUAGAGGAGGAGCAGAGAUGAAGAAAAGGAGAAGAAAAGCGCUGGAAAGAGAAGAAAAGGAACCUCCUUCUGUGCAGCAGGCUCCUGGCCCAGGGAGUGCGGUGUGCGGCAGAGUGCGUGCAGGGAAGCAGCCUCUGAAAUCGUGCAGGGAAGCACCCUGUGAAAUCGUGCAGGGAAGCACCCUGUGAAAUCGUGCAGGGAAGCACCCUGUGAAGUCGUGCAGGGAAGCACCCUCUGAAAUCGUGCAGGGAAGCACCCUCUGAAAUCGUGCAGGGAAGCACCCUGUGAAGUCGUGCAGGGAAGCACCUUCUGAAAUCGUGCAGGGAAGCACCCUCUGAAAUCGUGCAGGGAAGCACCCUCUGAAAUGCCUAGAAAUAGCUGCCGGGCUUUCACUUGGUUCCCAAAUUUCUUCAAAGGUCAAAACCAUCACAGUGGGCAACUUUACACCCCAGUGUUCACUGUCCUCAGGCCACUGCAGAGCCAUCCUAGUGGGGCAGUGGGCGCGGGGCGGGGGCUCCUGACUCCGGUGAGGUCACCCUGGAGGGGAGUCCCAGGAAUCAGCCUGAUGUUCAGAAUGCCUUCCUGGCAUCUCAGAAGUGUACUGGGGGAGACGUGAGGACCUUUCAGCCAAGUGUCAGCGUUCUUAUUGCAGGAGAACAUUAAAGCCACAACCCAGAAACUUCUCAGGAGCAUGGCGCACCCACACCAGCCCCGGGCUCCGCCUGGACAGCACCUCCUGGGCCGCCCUGACCAGCAGACACCAUCCUUCCAGCCUCUCUUGGCCACCCGGACCAGCGGGCACCACCCUCCCAGCCUCACGCGGCCACCCUGACCAGCAGGCACCAUCCUUCCAGCCUUGCUCAGUCACCCUGACCCAGAGGGCUGCCCUGACCAGCGGGCACCAUCCUCCCAGCCCCACUCAGCUGCCCUGACCAGCGGGCACCAUCCUCCCAGCCUCACUCGGCCAGCCGAGCUCUGUAGGCCUCAGAGUGCAGAGAACCUCAAAUGUUGUGACUUUGCUCUGCUGCAGGGACCUGCCAUGGAGUGUCCCUUGUGCGAGCAUUUUGAGAGCUAUGCCAGCAUCCAUCCCUGCAGGUCCCAUCCCUGAGCCAUUUCUCAGGAGAGCAGGAAGGGAGCAGGGAGAGGGGUGCUCCCAGCCAGCCCCGGAACCAGAGGUCUGGGGACGCAGCCGACCAGCCCUCCUUGUCUGGGCCUCUGUUUCCUCUUCGACACAGGGAAGCAGGGAGGGGCCGAUCAGCGACUUAGGCCUGUUGGCUGUGGUGGGGUCCACCUGCGUUUCUGGGGAGCCCACGGACCCUGGGGUGUACCUGGGUUUCAUUCCCAGUGACCUCUCCUAUUGGUCCCCAUUUGGGGCGCUGAGAUGUGAUCGUUUCUUUCCUGAGAAUGAGCUGAGGUAAAAACAUGCUGGGGAGGAAGAUGGGCCCUGGGGGCAGCGAGCUGCGCCUCUGCACCGGGAGAAAGGCCGUGUCCCCAGAGCUGAGGCGGUGGUGGGCAGGGCUCCUGAGAAGCCGGGGCAGGGCAGGGUGUCUCUGAGGUCAAUGAGGAACAGCUGAGGUCCAGGGACGCAGGAAGGAUGGGGUGAACUCCGGGAUGGGGCCGGCAGGGAGCCUCACGCUUACAGAGCCUGGUGUUGGCACUCUCCUGGCUUCCUCCGCAAACCUAGCCACGUGGUCAGGGAGCCCGGGCCUAGCAGACGGCCCCCACCUUGACAGAAUCCCCAGGGUCGUGCGUGGCGGUGGGGGCGACUUCACAGCCGAGACCGGGCCUAACGCUGCUGUCUCGCAGUCACCCCUGCAGGCCGCUCAGGGCAGGGCUCUGGCCUGACGGGGGUUCCUGGACACGCCUCUGAGCCGGCAGCCCCUACCCGCACCCGUGCACCUUCCACGCCCGUCUCCAGCAGCCCCUGCCCCCACCCGCACCCCUGCACCUGCCACGCCUGUCUCCGGCAGCCCCUGCCCGCACCCGCACCCCUGCACCUGCCACGCCCGUCUCCGGCAGCACCUGCCACGCCCGUCUCCGGCAGCACCUGCCACGCCCGUCUCCGGCAGCACCUGCCACGCCCGUCUCCGGCAGCCCCUGCCCGCACCCGCACCCCUGCACCUGCCACGCCCGUCUCCGGCAGCCCCUGCCUGCACCCGCACCCCUCACGGCUGUCUCCGGCAGCCCCUGCCCGCGCCCGCACCUCUGCACCUCCCACGCCCCUCUCCGGCAGCCCCUGCCCACACCCGCACCCCUGCACCUCCCACGCCCGUCUUGCCCUGGGGCCCAGGUGCAGGUCUGUGAGGAGGGCAGCCCCGUGCUCCCGUGGCCACCGCUCAGCCAAAUGGAUUCAGCGAGGGUUUUUAGUGUUUGUGCCUGUGUCCCCGUGUGCCUGUUUCCUGGUGAGGCUGGAUGCCUGGCAUGUCUGAACACUCACAUUCCCCAGGCAUGCAUGUGCAGCCGCCGCCGCCACCCAUGUACUGUGGCGCUGACCCCUCCUGUAACAGCUGUGGUCUUGGCCUCUCGUGUUGGUGGCAGAUGUCCCAUUUCCCAGUUACUUUCUGUUGUCCAAAAGUUUAACUGUCCUGCCAGCCAAAGCUGCUGAGCAUUACUCUGAUAGACCAUCAGUCCUUGGUAAGUGUCCUGUGCAUCUGGGAUAAGCAUCCGUUUGUUUUCAGCUGCGCUUUCUGUGACUUGCUCUGCGUGAGUCCUCGGUCCACGUGGGCCGUUGCGCUGGUUCCCAGCCUGCCCGACACACUCACUGCGACGCCUCCCUUGCCUACUGCUUGCUGGCUUCUGUGUUCUCUGCAGUAAACAUUGAUUUCUGACUCGA